AAACCAGAAACGGGAGUGGCUUGCGGAGCAGGAAUGCCGCAGCCGUGCCGCCAAGUUCGGAGGGAGAAGAAGCAGGUGGGGGACCGCAAAGCCCUGUUUCUAGAACUCCGGACGGAUUGUUCAGAAGUUUGUGGAAGAGCAGGCUGCCUUUCUCACUCAGAAUGUUUGUCUGCUUUGCUUUGCGUUAAAGAAUCUGCACCGUAGUUGAUGCAACUGAAGUUUAUAUAAGAAGUUUACAUUAACUCUUACCUAAGGAAGGACCCAUUCCAACAAUCUCGUAAAACAUGGUGGAUUACUAUGAAGUUCUAGGCGUGCAGAGACAUGCCUCACCCGAGGAUAUUAAAAAGGCAUAUCGGAAACUGGCACUGAAGUGGCAUCCAGAUAAAAAUCCUGAGAAUAAAGAAGAAGCAGAGAGAAAAUUCAAGCAAGUAGCGGAGGCAUAUGAAGUGCUGUCGGAUGCUAAGAAACGGGACAUCUAUGACAAAUAUGGCAAAGAAGGAUUAAAUGGUGGAGGAGGAGGUGGAAGUCAUUUUGACAGUCCAUUUGAAUUUGGCUUCACAUUCCGUAACCCAGAUGAUGUCUUCAGGGAAUUUUUUGGUGGAAGGGACCCAUUUUCAUUUGACUUCUUUGAAGACCCUUUUGAGGACUUCUUUGGGAAUCGAAGGGGUCCCCGAGGAAGCAGAAGCCGAGGGACGGGGUCGUUUUUCUCUGCGUUCAGUGGAUUUCCGUCUUUUGGAAGUGGAUUUUCUUCUUUUGAUACAGGAUUUACUUCAUUUGGGUCACUAGGUCACGGGGGCCUCACUUCAUUCUCUUCCACGUCAUUUGGUGGUAGUGGCAUGGGCAACUUCAAAUCGAUAUCAACUUCAACUAAAAUGGUUAAUGGCAGAAAAAUCACUACAAAGAGAAUUGUCGAGAACGGUCAAGAAAGAGUAGAAGUUGAAGAAGAUGGCCAGUUAAAGUCCUUAACAAUAAAUGGUGUGGCCGACGACGAUGCCCUCGCUGAGGAGCGCAUGCGGAGAGGCCAGAACGCCCUGCCAGCCCAGCCUGCCGGCCUCCGCCCGCCGAAGCCGCCCCGGCCUGCCUCGCUGCUGAGACACGCGCCUCACUGUCUCUCUGAGGAGGAGGGCGAGCAGGACCGACCUCGGGCACCCGGGCCCUGGGACCCCCUCGCGUCCGCAGCAGGUGUGCAAAGGGAGGCAGCCGUGGAGCAGGCGCAGAGUGAGACUUCUCUGGGUGCCAGAGGACAGCGAGGACACAAACCGCGCCUGGGCUGCUGUGUUCUGACCUGAGCGGGCGUGGGCGGUCGGGCGGGGCGGGAGGAGGUAGCCUCGCUCUGCUCCUCUCCCGCUCGCGGCGCCCCACGCCACGGUGGCUCCGGGCCCCCCACCGUUAAAACGGGGUCCGCGUGUCCUGUACGCAGCGUGUUGCUCCGCAAAGGAUGACAGAGCUGCCACGGCAGUGCGAGGUGCUGCUUUUACCGUAGACGUGCCUUUUCGUAGCUUUCAGCGUAGAGCUUGAGGCCUGUGGCUUAGGCCGGGUGGUCUCGUGCUGGUGGGGUCUGCGUUUGCCCCUGCCCCUCCGUCAGCUUCACCUUCUCGUGCCUUCUUCUGCGCUGGGUGCAGAACAAAAGACCCCCUCAAGUCAAGCCUCCUUGUGAAGCGUAGUCUGCCCGCCCACCCCCCGUGGGGUUCUUGGCCGCCCUGCCCUCCUCCCACCUGUUAGGGAGCCGGAUAGUCUCUGAAGUGAGUGCCCCGGAGAAGUUCUGGGUCACCCUGAGGACGUGCUGUGCAUGUAGGCUUGGCCCUGACUGCGUCCUAAAGCCCAGGGUCCAUGUAGUGUGAAUCGUGCGUCAGUUGGAAGUAUUUGUGCCUCUUCUGGUUCUUAUCACCGCACGCGGUGAGGUGACCCCAGCCGCUCAUGUCGUGCAGGAAGACAUGGAUGGUUGAUCCCUGGGUUUGGGGGACCGAAGCGGAUGUCGUGAGGUUACUUCUGUGGACUUGGGCCGAACAGCACUGUCUAAGCAGGACAUGAAAAGAAGGGGGAAGCGUCUCUCCUUUUCCCUUCAUGGAACUUUCCAUUGAAAAAUUAGCCCCUUCCAGUCCUUCUCGGAUGAAGCACAGUUGCCGGUUACGCUUCCGAGGAGGACGGAAGGUGCACCCCCAGCCGUGAGAGCCUCAGGAUGUGCCGCCUGUGGGUGGGCACGGCAGCCCCUCCAGCCGGCCGCCCACCUGCCGUGCUGCGCUCACCUUUGCUGUGUGAGUCUGUGCUGUGUCACUGAGUGACAGACAGAGGCAGUUGCAGGCUGCAUGCACCCAGAAAGAACUCCCCCUGCACUAAGCGGGCAUGGGGGAGGCUCCCCAGGGUCCCUGCACUGAGCGGGGUGGGGGAGGCUCCCCACGGUUCCCUGCACUGAGCGGGGUGGGGGAGACUCCCCACGGUUCCCUGCACUGAGCGGGCGUGGGGAAGGUUCCCAGGAUCCCUGCACUGAGCGGGGUGGGGGAGACUCCCCACGGUUCCCUGCACUGAGCGGGCGUGGGGAAGGUUCCCAGGAUCCCUGCACUGAGCGGGCGUGGGGAAGGUUCCCAGGAUCCCUGCACUGAGCGGGCGUAGGGGAGGCUCCCCAGGAUCCCUGCACUGAGCGGGCGUUGGGGAGGCUCCCCAGGGUCUGUUGUGCGCUCCUGGUACUGGAGGGUCUGAUGGCCGUAGGGAGGGUGCACUGUUUGUCGAUGGGUCUUUGCAAGGUGCAGGAUAGAGCAGGGUUGUAGCUGUAGUGUCCCUGAACCACUGGGGUUAGGAGGCCACCGGAAGCCUGGCCUGCUAGGGGCCUUGUGAUUUCGCAGGCCCCGAGAACGUGGUGUGCAGGUGCGGGCCGCCUGGGGGAGCCAUGUUUAAAGUGCGGUGAGGCUCCUGGAACGGCACCCACCGCAGGCCCGAGGCCACACCUGUAUGUCAGAACUGGGCGGGUCUUCUCCUCCCAGGCCUUCAGCGCCUGUGGCUAUGGCUGUGGGCGGGACUGAUACGGGCAGGCAGGCGCUGUUCUCCCCACGUAUUCUCGGCUUCCCCGCCAUACACCGUUUCUGAGUGGGGAGAACUGGUUGACUGCUGAAUCCCAACACAAAUCCUUAGAGCAAAGAGGCCAGUGAUGGCUUUUGUUUCUGCCCGGAUCCUCUUUGUGGAUCUUCCGUUUUGCGGCUUUUCCUCUCAUUUGUUUCCUUUUUUUAAUCGCUUCAUGAGAUCUUGAAGAUACCAAAGUAACCAUCAAAGAUUUAAAGACGUGAUUUUUAUACAAAUAUAUAACGAACACGUCAGAGACUUUUACUUAAGUUCUUACUGAGAGAUGACAAAGCUGACUCAAAGGAUGAGUCAAGAAACCGCUGCAGAGUUGGAGACAGAACUGGAGUGAAAUUGCAAAGCAGGGUGGUUUUGGUCUCUGCAGAGGCCAUUUGCGACUCACUCACCAACUCCGGUGUCAGGGUGCUGGUGGGUGACAGGGAAGAGGUUGAGCAAGCCUCCGCCCCUGCAGGCUCGCUCAUUAUACAAUGAGCACCUGCACCACCAAAUCCGAACAACUGUACAUGCUUACAGAGAAGGGCACGUGCUAGUGUGGGAGUGACAAAGUCACACGGGUGCAGACCCCUUAGCUCCAGCCUGCUGGGUGUUCUGACGAAUGGACUUUGUAGCGAUAACACAGGCUCCUGAGUCAGGAUACUGGUUUGCUGCAUUUCUGCGUCACUGAAGGUCUCGCUUUCCCCGAAGCCCCUUGUCACAGAAAACCCAUGACUCUUGGCCAGGCCUCUGGGUGCCUGGAAGAUCCCACUAUCAUCUUUUUGUGGGAUUUGCAUGUCCUGGUCAAGGUUCCUGUAAAAGGAAUACAGUGAGGAGACCGGCCACCCGACAGUAUUGAUGGCCCCCACUUUGGCCUCCAGCCGUCUGACCCGUCCCUGAAUCGAGCAGGUCCUGUCGGAGCUCCCAGGAGUGAGCGAGCUUCCACUCACAGGGUCACAGCCAGGUGUGCAGCCCCCAGGCCUGGGCGGUUCUAGGGCAUGAUUUUUUUUAGGCUGGAAAUGAGCUCUCACUUGAGAUGCACCCCUCAAAAUACUGAACGUACUGCUUCUGUGAGAAUUUCCCCUCCUUGUGUCUGGUGUGAUUGACAACGGGUGCAGCCAGUGGAAGCAGGAAUGUCGGGGAGCGCGGGGUGCAGGGGGUGCCCUGUCACAGUCAGCGGGGAGCGCCUGUCCCUGCUGCGUGGUGUGGGGUUCCCGUGGCUGGCAUUUGCUGCUGUGUGGAGUCCUCAAACCCAGCGCUCGCCCUGCCUGCGUUCAGAGGACAGAGGCACCACCGGGAACCCACCGGAUCCUCACUCAGGCUUUGGAAAGGCCGAGUGAUGUUUUGUGUUUGUGAAUUCCACACAUACUGUAGGAGUAUCAAGAACACGUAACUGUUAAAAAAGGAAAAGUAAAAUUACUGAACAGGAAAGAAAGAAUAAAGCAGGUCCUUUGUUUUUUUGGCUGAGGAAAGCAGCCUGCCCUGGAACGCUGUAGAAUGUCUCCCUUUUUGUGAAGCACAGCAUGGAGCUCUCGGAACUGAAGAUGGGAAUCUAACCCUGCCCUCAGCUUUCAACAGCUCGAAGUUUGUCUUUUUAAUGAAACUAAUUUGUGUAUUUAUACUUAAGGGUUUUCAAGUCCUUAAACUUGAUAAGAAAACUUAAGUCGUUUUCUAUCAGGACAAGUUUUUAAGUAGUCACUGGUGGGAGAGCGUGCCUCUGUGGACUGUGCCCAAGGCUGGCGGUCCCACGAAGUCCCAGAGCCCGCGAGCCGGUGCCCAAGGCCAUGUCUGUGAUUUGCAGGAGGUUCAGGUGACAGGAAGGCCUGCUCUGUUUUUCUCACUUCAAUUUUGGACUUUUUUUUUUUUUUUUUUUUUUUUGAGACAGUCUCGCUCUGUCGCCCAGGCUGGAGUGCAGUGGCGUGAUCUCGGCUCACUGCAACCUCUGCCUCAAGGGUUCCAGCGAUUUUCCUGCCUCACCUCCCCAGUGGCCGGAACUACAGGUGCUUGCCACCACUUCUGGCUCAUUUUUGUAUUUUUAGUAGAGAUGUGGUUUCUCCAUGUUGGACUGGCUGCUCUCGAACUCCUGACCUCAGGUGAUCCCCCCGCUUCAGCCUCCCAAAGUGCUGGGAUUACAGGCGGGAGCCACCGCGCCCGGCAAUAGUGGAGGCUUGAAGAACACCGGAAAGUGGUUUCCUUGUACCGGACCCGCCCCUCCCCCACCAUCCCGGCAGCCCCAGGGCGGGUGAGGGCGACUGCAGUGUGGUCACCUCAGGCUUUCCGUCCCUAGCUCAUAAAGGCCCAGUGGCAGCAGUUGCUUUAAAGGAGCUCCGUUACUCCCUUUGUUCUGGGGUCUUGGUAAAGUUUGCUUUGCUGAAGCGGAGGAACCGCAGGCGGUGCUGACCCCCCCACCCCGCCCCCAUCCCACGGGGUCCCUUGGGUCCCGGGGCACGAGGCUCCUCUGAGGGACACGGCCUCCAAGAGCUGGCUCUGCCCUGGCCGCCCUCCACAGUCACGGCGGCUCCCCGCAUGCUCCUCGGGACGGAGAUCUCCUGGCUUCCUCCCGCUUCCUUUCCUCUGCGUUUUCCGCAGAGCCGCCUCCCUGCUUUGGAAGCAGGUACUCAGCGGCCUCUGCAGCCGCCAACGGCACACAGGCCUCUCUCUGUUCGUUCUUUCUUUCCGUAACCGUAGCUUGAGGCACAUUUCCUAAAUAUGCAGCAUGGAACGCUUGGCGGUUCUGAACGCGCAUCUCGUGCUGCUCCUGUAGGGCGGUUAGGACGCGCUCCUCUGGCGAGGAAGGUGGCAGCCUCCACUGUGCACGGGUCA